AAAGGAGGAAGGACAGCACAGCUGACAGCCGUGCUCAGAAAGUUUCUGGAUCCCAGGCUCAUCUCCACAGAGGAGAACACGCAGGCAGCAGAGACCAUGGGGCCCAUCUCAGCCCCUUCCUGCAGAUGGCGCAUCCCCUGGCAGGGGCUCCUGCUCACAGCCUCACUUUUCACCUUCUGGAACCCGCCCACCACUGCUCAGCUCACUAUUGAAGCUGUGCCAUCCAAUGCUGCAGAGGGGAAGGAGGUUCUUCUACUUGUCCACAAUCUGCCCCAGGACCCUCGUGGCUACAACUGGUACAAAGGGGAAACAGUGGAUGCCAACCGUCGAAUUAUAGGAUAUGUAAUAUCAAAUCAACAGAUUACCCCAGGGCCUGCAUACAGCAAUCGAGAGACAAUAUACCCCAAUGCAUCCCUGCUGAUGCGGAACGUCACCAGAAAUGACACAGGAUCCUACACCCUACAAGUCAUAAAGCUAAAUCUUAUGAGUGAAGAAGUAACUGGCCAGUUCAGCGUACAUCCGGAGACUCCCAAGCCCUCCAUCUCCAGCAACAACUCCAACCCCGUGGAGGACAAGGAUGCUGUGGCCUUCACCUGUGAACCUGAGACUCAGAACACAACCUACCUGUGGUGGGUAAAUGGUCAGAGUCUCCCGGUCAGUCCCAGGCUGCAGCUGUCCAAUGGCAACAGGACCCUCACUCUACUCAGUGUCACAAGGAAUGACGUAGGACCCUAUGAAUGUGAAAUACAGAACCCAGCGAGUGCAAACUUCAGUGACCCAGUCACCCUGAAUGUCCUCUAUGGCCCAGAUGCCCCCACCAUUUCCCCUUCAGACACCUAUUACCAUGCAGGGGUAAAUCUCAACCUCUCCUGCCAUGCGGCCUCUAAUCCACCCUCACAGUAUUCUUGGUCUGUCAAUGGCACAUUCCAGCAAUACACACAAAAGCUCUUUAUCCCCAACAUCACUACAAAGAACAGCGGAUCCUAUGCCUGCCACACCACUAACUCAGCCACUGGCCGCAACAGGACCACAGUCAGGAUGAUCACAGUCUCUGAUGCUUUAGUACAAGGAAGUUCUCCUGGCCUCUCAGCUAGAGCCACUGUCAGCAUCAUGAUUGGAGUACUGGCCAGGGUGGCUCUGAUAUAGUAGCUCUGGUGUAGUUUCUGCAUUUCAAGAAGACUGGCAGACAGUUGUUUUUAUUCUUCCUCAAAGCAUUUGCAAUCAGCUACCAUUCAAAAUUGCUUCUUCUUCAAGAUUUAUGGAAAAUACUCUGACGAGUACUCUUGAACACAAGUUCCUGAUAACUUUAAGAUCACGCCACUGGACUGUCUAUGAACUUGCAAACAGGCUGAUACCUUUGUGAAGUUGCCCACCAAAACACAGAAGGAAAAAAACAUGAAUUUCAUUGAACUAAAUAAUAAUGAGGAUAAUGUUUUUAAGAUUUUUUUUUUUUUUUUUUUGAGAUGGAAUCUCGCUCUGUCGCCCAGGCUGGAGUGCAGUGGCACGAUCUCAACUCACUGCAAGCUCCGCCUCCUGGGUUCACACCAUUCUCCUGCCUCAGCCUCCUGAGUAGCUGGGACUACAGGCGCCUGCCACAACGCCCGGCUAAUUUUUUGUAUUUUUAGUAGAGACGGGGUUUCACUGUGGUCUCAAUCUCCUGACUUCAUGGUCCGCCUGCCUCAGCCUCCCAAAGUUCUGGGAUUACAGGUGUGAGCCACCGCGCCCAGCCCGUUUUUAAGAUUUUUUAUUUGAAAAAUUGCCAAUUCUUUAAGUGUUUUCUUUUUCAGAUUUAUGAAUUUCUUUAUCUUUUAAGCUAUCUAUACCUUACUGCAAUUUGGUAAAGCAGACUUUUGUGAACAAAAAUUAUAACAUUUACUUUUGCUCCCUACCUGACUGCCACAGAACUGGGCAACUAUUCAUGAGUAUUCAUAUGUUUAUGGUAAUUCAGUUAUUUGCACAAGUUCAGUGAGAAUCUGCUGUCUUUAUAAUGGGAUAUAGUUUAAAACAUUGGUUAUAUUACCAAGGCUUUGAUUGGGAUGUUAUAUUUGAGAAAAUACAGAGAAUGAUAGAUUAACGGAGUGUCUAAUCUAUCGUGUCAACCCCAAAUUUUUACGUAUGAGAUCCUUUAGUCCACCCAAUGGCUGACAGUAACAGCAUCUUUAACACAACUCUUUGUUCAAAUGUACUAUGGUCUCUUUUAGAGUCAGACUCCUAGACUCACUUGUUCUCACUGUCUGUUUUAAUUUAACCCAGGCAUGCAAUGCUAGAUAAUAAAAUUGCUCCCUAUUGGCUGAUCA